AUUCAGAGGCGCGGGGCCGGGCCCGGCGGACGCUUGUUGUUGUCCGGCCGGGGGAGGCGGAGGUCGCUCGCUCGCUCGCUCGGCUCGCUGACUCGCCGGAGCGCUCUGUGGCGGUCGGCGGCAGGUCGGUCGCGAGAGCGGGCUCUGUGGAAGGGGGCGAGGCUAUGUCGCGGUGGCAGCCCGGAUGGGCCGGCAGGGCCGGGAGUAACGGGACGUCGCCGCGGAGCUUCUUCCCCCGGAUACAGUGCGGCCCGAGCGGAGGCCGCGGCGCCGCCCUCCGAUCUUGAAGAGCCCGCGCUGCGCGGAGCCCGCCCCCGCCUGCGCACCGGCACCGACGCGGAGCGACCCAGCCCAGCCAGACCCGGCCCGGCGCGGCCUGAUCUAACCCAGCCAGGCAGGCAAUACUAGCCCCUCUGGAGCACGGAGCUCCUUCCCCAAAGACAUGAAGCUAUUGGAGAACUCGAGCUUUGAAGCCAUCAACUCACAGCUGACUGUGGAGACUGGAGAUGCCCACAUCAUUGGCAGGAUUGAGAGCUACUCAUGUAAGAUGGCAGGAGACGACAAACACAUGUUCAAGCAGUUCUGCCAGGAGGGCCAGCCCCACGUGCUGGAGGCACUUUCUCCACCCCAGACUUCAGGACUGAGCCCCAGCAGACUCAGCAAAAGCCAAGGCGGUGAGGAGGAGGGCCCCCUCAGUGACAAGUGCAGCCGCAAGACCCUCUUCUACCUGAUUGCCACGCUCAAUGAGUCCUUCAGGCCUGACUAUGACUUCAGCACAGCCCGCAGCCAUGAGUUCAGCCGGGAGCCCAGCCUUAGCUGGGUGGUGAAUGCAGUCAACUGCAGUCUGUUCUCAGCUGUGCGGGAGGACUUCAAGGAUCUGAAACCACAGCUGUGGAACGCGGUGGACGAGGAGAUCUGCCUGGCUGAAUGUGACAUCUACAGCUAUAACCCAGACUUGGACUCAGAUCCCUUCGGGGAGGAUGGUAGCCUCUGGUCCUUCAACUACUUCUUCUACAACAAGCGGCUCAAGCGAAUCGUCUUCUUUAGCUGCCGUUCCAUCAGUGGCUCCACCUACACACCCUCAGAGGCAGGCAACGAGCUGGACAUGGAGCUGGGGGAGGAGGAGGUGGAGGAAGAAAGCAGAAGCGGGGGCAGUGGGGCCGAGGAGACCAGCACCAUGGAGGAGGACAGGGUCCCAGUGAUCUGUAUUUGAUGAGGAGGAGCCGAGGCCCCAGCUUCAUCCAGCUUCAACCAAUGCCUGGACCUGUCCACCUGAGAGGCCCCUGGGGCCUCCCCAGCUGCUGGCCAGACCCUGGCGCUGCCACAGUCCUGGCACUGCCCAAGGCCAUACCUGCCUAGCCCUUUGGCUCCAUCCUGUGGAUGCCCACUCACCCCUCAGACUCCUGCUGCCCAUGCUGUGGCCGGACUUGUCAGCAGGGGGCCUGGUGGGAGGAGCGACUGCCCUGCCCAAAUGAACUGCCACAGCAGGGACAGCUGGACCGCAGAGUUUAUUUUUGUAUUUCUACUGGGCCUGCACACUCCAGCCCAAAGGGUCUGUGGCCGGAGGCCCCACGAGCAGGCCCCAGCAGUCACCGGCUCUGGUCUUGGGCCGGCCCCGGUGCCCACCUGUACCCCCACCUCGCCCAUUUGGCCGCGUGCACUGAGUGUCACUUUGCUGCAGCUCGUUUCUUUCCAAUAAAAGUUUCUGUGACUUA